AGUCCAGGCCCGGCUUCCUCCAGGUCUCCCGGCAACGGCUGCGGCCUCGCCCACGUUAUGGCGCCCGAGGAGAACGCGGGGACCGAACUCUUGCUGCAGGGUUUUGAGCGCCGCUUCCUGGCGGUGCGCACACUGCGCUCCUUCCCCUGGCAGAGCUUAGAGGCAAAGUUAAGAGACUCAUCAGAUUCUGAGCUGCUGCGGGAUAUUUUGCAGAAGACUGUGAGGCAUCCUGUGUGUGUGAAGCACCCGCCGUCAGUCAAGUAUGCCUGGUGCUUUCUCUCAGAACUCAUCAAAAAGCACGAGGCUGUCCACACGGAGCCUUUGGACAAACUGUACGAGGUGCUCGCGGAGACUCUGAUGGCCAAGGAGUCCACCCAGGGCCACCGGAGCUAUUUGCUGUCCUCAGGAGGCUCAGUCACACUCUCCAAGAGCACAGCCAUCAUCUCCCACGGUACCACAGGCCUGGUCACAUGGGAUGCCGCCCUCUACCUUGCAGAAUGGGCCAUCGAGAACCCGGCAGCCUUCAUUAACAGGACUGUCCUAGAGCUUGGCAGUGGUGCCGGCCUCACAGGCCUUGCCAUCUGCAAGAUGUGCCGCCCCCGGGCAUACAUCUUCAGCGACCCUCACAGCCGGAUCCUCGAGCAGCUCCGAGGGAAUGUCCUUCUCAAUGGCCUCUCAUUAGAGGCAGACAUCACUGGCAACUUAGACAGCCCCAGGGUGACAGUGGCCCAGCUGGACUGGGACGUAGCAAUGGUCCAUCAGCUCUCUGCCUUCCAGCCAGAUGUUGUCAUUGCAGCAGACGUGCUGUAUUGCCCAGAAGCCAUCGUGUCGCUGGUCGGGGUCCUGCAGAGGCUGGCUGCCUGCCGGGAGCACAAGCGGGCUCCUGAGGUCUACGUGGCCUUUACCGUCCGCAACCCAGAGACAUGCCAGCUGUUCACCACCGAGCUAGGCCGGGAUGGGAUCAGAUGGGAAGCGGAAGCUCAUCAUGACCAGAAACUGUUUCCCUAUGGAGAGCACUUGGAGAUGGCAAUGCUGAACCUCACACUGUAGGACUCACACAUGACUCCAAAGGGAUUGUGAGAAUCAAGUCACUCUCGUGGGAAGAAUUUUUAUAUGGGAAAGUGGAUAAAACUUUCAUUGGACUGGAAUGUUUGGAGAUUAUUAAACUCCAAAUCAGGAAUCAAAACUGCCCUCUAAUAAGACAUUAGCUGUCUAGGCGUGUGGGUGCCCCCUUUCUGCCAGCAGUUCUGGUUCUCAAGAAAAUCAUCAUAAAUCAGACAUGAAAAUUCUAGCUCCAAAAAUAGCAUUUUCUUUCUGCAAAUAAAAACGUGUGUAUCAAGGAUGACGUUCCCCCAACGUGGACACACUCAGUUCCUCAGAAAGCCAAGCCCGCUGCAGCUGCCACAUCCCUGGACACACUCGGUUCCUCACAAAGCCAAGCCCGCUGCAGCUGCCACAUCCCUGGACACACUCGGUUCCUCACAAAGCCAAGCCCGCUGCAGCUGCCACAUCCCUGGACACACUCGGUUCCUCACAAAGCCAAGCCCGCUGCAGCUGCCACAUCCCAGGGCUUAUGGUGCAGCAGGCGCUUUUUUCAAGACAGGAAUGAAAGUGUUAGGAACACGGCAGAAAGGUGACACCUGGAGACCAAAUGCAGGAUGAGGAGUACUGCAGAGGUCACAGGGAAGUCACAGAACAGUAAUACGCUAGCAGGGGCAUGGGGCAUGAAGAACAGAAGACAGGAAGCAUUUCAGAGACUCCAAAGAAGAAAUCAGGGCCAACCACAGCUUCCCGGGUCAUUCACCAGGUGACACCACUGCCGUCAUUUCAGCUUCUGGCCACUGGGAGGCGCUGCUCGAAAGGCUUUGCCCUGAGACCCCAAGAAGCUGCGGGAAGGACAGCAGGGGCCCUGGGGUUUUAGCCUCUGGCCCAGGAGUUAUGUGUCCAUAACCAAAGGGAGCACAGUCUGCACCCAGCUCUCAUCCCAUCAGAGCUGCUGAGACUCUUGCAGGUUCUUCCAGAACUGGUUUAGCUUGCCUGCAGGAUCAGAAAAGUUUGAGAAAAGCAUCUGCAAAAUGCUAAAGAGCAGAGCUUAACUCAUUGCCUGUCCCCACCCCAUCCCAGGUCACCACUUGGCUGACCCCAGGUCCCCGACCCAACAACAACCCCUCCCAAGUCCCUAACUCCCUCACUUGGACUUGAGACCCUUCACAACCCAGCAGCGCUCCACCUCCAACUUGACAUCAUGCUUUCUGGAAACUUCCCCGUAUGUCCCACUUUCCCACACUUGGUGCCCUGGAGCACCUUCCGGCCUCUACAUGCUGUACGUUCCCCUGUGAGCACCCUCCUCUCGGCCUCUGGCCAACACAGUCCCACCCAUCUGUGGGUAACAAGGGGGUGUGGGUGUUCUUUUCAGCCUUGCUAAACUGUCUGAAUCAAGGAUCACAAACUACAGCCUGCAGGCCAAAUCCAGCCCACAGCCUGUGUUUGUAAAUAAAGCUUUGUUGGAACAAAGCCA